GAACGGGAGAUGUUGCAGGCGCCGAGAGGGCGGGCCAGGGCCGCACUCCGGAGACUCGCGGUUGCUACGCGCACCAUGGCUGGAGCGCCCACGGUCUCGCUUCCUGAACUCCGUUCACUCCUAGCCUCCGGACGGGCCCGGCUCUUCGACGUGCGCUCUCGCGAGGAGGCGGCAGCUGGGACCAUCCCAGGGGCGCUCAACAUCCCGGUGUCCGAGUUGGAGAGUGCUCUGCAGAUGGAGCCAGCUGCCUUCCAGGCUUUAUAUUCUGCUGAGAAGCCAAAGCUGGAAGAUGAGCAUCUCGUUUUCUUCUGUCAGAUGGGCAAGCGGGGCCUCCAGGCCACGCAGCUGGCCCGGAGUCUUGGAUACACUGGGUACGGGGAGGUGUGGCUGCUAGCUGGGAGGUGAUGGGGACUGCCUGUCAUUCCUGUCAGUCUCUCACGCUUCUUUGUCUCCACAGGGCUCGCAACUACGCUGGAGCCUAUAGAGAAUGGUUGGAGAAAGAGAGUUAGGCAGGAGGCAGCUUACUGAUUGCCACCCCCUGGCCCCUUAAUGGCCACCUUAACUAAGGGUGUGAACGGGCUGACUUGGUGAAUUGGGCAACUCCUUAUAGUGUUGUGCACACAAAAGCAUCAAAUAAAGAACAUUUAAUCAAA